ACUUAACAACCGAAGUAACCCGCAAUGCGGAAGGGCGAGGGGAUUGCGAGUCACCGAGUUUCCCGCGCGGCUUGAGUCACGGCCUAGAAAGAGAGAUGUUGGGGUUCCCAGGACCAGGACAGAGGUGGUAGUGAACUCUCAUGGGCAUCCAGAGAAGGUCAGGCCCCUUGCUGACAGGCCUAUCUGUGGGGCUACUGCUGCUCUUCAGCUGGGUGACCCUUGUCCAGCCAACCUCUCUCUCAGCUCUGGUCCACCACCCUCACUUGUGCCAGACCACCCGGGAUGUCCAUGGCCGUCACUACCCUGGUUUCUUUUGCCCUCGUCUGUCUGAUUCUCCAGAGGAAGCCUACUGCUGCCACCUGCAGGCUGCAGGGGGCUCCUGCUGCACCCGGGCUGAAUUUGAGGCCCUGUACCAAGUCAAUCUGUCCGCUCUUCCGCCCCCGCCCAUCCUCAGGGGCCCAGGCCCGCUCCUAGUGCUGGGCCUCUACAACCUACUGGUUGUGACCCUGAUGACCGUAGACCUCGUGCACUUCUGCUGCGGUCGGGGCCGGAGUCUGGGCUGGAGCCACCGCAGGCCUCCCUCUGGGUCCUCCGCCGCGAGCUCCCUGCAGGUCUCUGCGGGGACAGCUUAGGUGCGCCCGGAGCUUGCCUGCACCUGCGAUCCAGAGCCAAGCGCCCCGCCCCUGCCCGGGCGCGCUCCCUCCUUAGCCCUGCCCCUCUCUGACCCCACCUCCGACGCAAGAGUGGGGCGGGGCAGCUGCCGGUGGCGUCCCGAACCCAGACUCGCCCCGCCCCAGAGACUGCGCCUGCGCGGGCACGAGACAACCUCUCCGCGAUGACUGUGAGUGGUCCAGGGACCCCCGAGCCCCGGCCGGCCACCCCCGGGGCCAGCUCAGUGGAGCAGCUGCGGAAGGAGGGCAAUGAGCUGUUCAAAUGUGGAGACUACGGGGGCGCCCUGGCGGCCUACACUCAGGCCCUGGGUCUGGACGCGACGCCCCAGGACCAGGCCGUUCUGCACCGGAACCGGGCCGCCUGCCACCUCAAGCUGGAAGAUUACGACAAAGCAGAAACAGAGGCAUCCAAAGCCAUUGAAAAGGAUGGUGGGGAUGUCAAAGCACUCUACCGGCGGAGCCAAGCCCUAGAGAAGCUGGGCCGCCUGGACCAGGCUGUCCUUGACCUGCAGAGAUGUGUGAGCUUGGAGCCCAAGAACAAAGUUUUCCAGGAGGCCUUGCGGAACAUCGGGGGCCAGAUUCAGGAGAAGGUGCGAUACAUGUCCUCGACGGAUGCCAAAGUGGAACAGAUGUUUCAGAUACUGUUGGACCCAGAAGAGAAGGGCACUGAGAAAAAGCAAAAGGCUUCUCAGAACCUGGUGGUGCUGGCCAGGGAGGAUGCUGGAGCGGAGAAGAUCUUCCGGAGUAAUGGGGUUCAGCUCUUGCAACGUUUACUGGACAUGGGAGAGACUGACCUCAUGCUGGCGGCUCUGCGUACGCUGGUUGGCAUUUGCUCUGAGCAUCAGUCACGGACAGUGGCAACCCUGAGCAUACUGGGAACUCGGCGAGUAGUCUCCAUCCUGGGCGUGGAAAGCCAGGCUGUGUCCCUGGCUGCCUGCCACCUGCUGCAGGUUAUGUUUGAUGCCCUCAAGGAAGGUGUCAAAAAAGGCUUCCGAGGCAAAGAAGGUGCCAUCAUUGUGGAUCCUGCCCGGGAGCUGAAGGUCCUCAUCAGUAACCUCUUAGAUCUGCUGACAGAGGUGGGGGUCUCUGGCCAAGGCCGAGACAAUGCCCUGACCCUCCUGAUUAAAGCGGUGCCCCGGAAGUCUCUCAAGGACCCCAACAACAGCCUCACCCUCUGGGUCAUCGACCAAGGUCUGAAAAAGAUUUUGGAAGUGGGGGGCUCUCUACAGGACCCUCCUGGGGAGCUCGCAGUGACCGCAAACAGCCGCAUGAGCGCCUCUAUUCUCCUCAGCAAGCUCUUUGAUGACCUCAAGUGUGAUGCGGAGAGGGAGAAUUUCCACAGACUUUGUGAAAACUACAUCAAGAGCUGGUUUGAGGGCCAAGGGCUGGCCGGGAAGCUACGGGCCAUCCAGACGGUGUCCUGCCUCCUGCAGGGCCCAUGUGACGCUGGCAACCGGGCCUUGGAGCUGAGCGGUGUCAUGGAGAGUGUGAUUGCUCUGUGUGCCUCUGAGCAGGAGGAGGAGCAGCUGGUGGCCGUGGAGGCUCUGAUCCAUGCAGCCGGCAAGGCUAAGCGGGCCUCAUUCAUCACUGCCAAUGGUGUCUCGCUGCUGAAGGACCUAUAUAAGUGCAGCGAGAAGGACAGCAUCCGCAUCCGGGCGCUAGUGGGACUCUGUAAGCUCGGUUCGGCUGGAGGGACUGACUUCAGCAUGAAGCAGUUUGCUGAAGGCUCCACUCUCAAACUGGCUAAGCAGUGUCGAAAGUGGCUGUGCAAUGACCAGAUCGACGCAGGCACUCGGCGCUGGGCAGUGGAGGGCCUGGCUUACCUGACCUUUGAUGCCGACGUGAAGGAAGAGUUUGUGGAGGAUGCGGCUGCUCUGAAAGCUCUGUUCCAGCUCAGCAGGUUGGAGGAGAGGUCAGUGCUCUUUGCGGUGGCCUCAGCGCUGGUGAACUGCACCAACAGCUAUGACUACGAGGAGCCCGACCCCAAGAUGGUGGAGCUGGCCAAGUAUGCCAAGCAGCAUGUGCCCGAGCAGCACCCCAAGGACAAGCCAAGCUUCGUGCGGGCUCGGGUGAAGAAGCUGCUGGCAGCGGGUGUGGUGUCGGCCAUGGUGUGCAUGGUGAAGACGGAGAGCCCUGUGCUGACCAGUUCCUGCAGAGAGCUGCUCUCCAGGGUCUUCUUGGCUUUAGUGGAAGAGGUAGAGGACCGAGGCACUGUGGUUGCCCAGGGAGGCGGCAGGGCGCUGAUCCCGCUGGCCCUGGAAGGCACGGACGUGGGGCAGACAAAGGCAGCCCAGGCCCUUGCCAAGCUCACCAUCACCUCCAACCCGGAGAUGACCUUCCCUGGCGAGCGGAUCUAUGAGGUGGUCCGGCCCCUCGUCUCCCUGUUGCACCUCAACUGCUCAGGCCUGCAGAACUUCGAGGCGCUCAUGGCCCUAACAAACCUGGCUGGGAUCAGCGAGAGGCUCCGGCAGAAGAUCCUGAAGGAGAAGGCUGUGCCCAUGAUAGAAGGCUACAUGUUUGAGGAGCAUGAGAUGAUCCGCCGGGCAGCCACGGAGUGCAUGUGUAACUUGGCCAUGAGCAAGGAGGUGCAGGACCUCUUCGAAGCCCAGGGCAAUGACCGACUGAAGCUGCUGGUGCUGUACAGUGGAGAGGAUGAUGAGCUGCUACAGCGGGCAGCUGCCGGGGGCUUGGCCAUGCUUACCUCCAUGCGGCCCACGCUCUGCAGCCGCAUUCCCCAAGUGACCACACACUGGCUGGAGAUCCUGCAGGCCCUGCUUCUGAGCUCCAACCAGGAGCUGCAGCACCGGGGUGCUGUGGUGGUGCUGAACAUGGUGGAGGCCUCGAGGGAGAUUGCCAGCACCCUGAUGGAGAGUGAGAUGAUGGAGAUCUUGUCAGUGCUAGCUAAGGGUGACCACAGCCCUGUCACAAGGGCUGCUGCAGCCUGCCUGGACAAAGCAGUGGAAUAUGGGCUUAUCCAACCCAACCAAGAUGGAGAGUGAGGGGGUUGUCCCUGGGCCCAAGGCUCAUGCACACGCUACCUAUUGUGGCACGGAGAGUAAGGACGGAAGCAGCUUUGGCUGGUGGUGGCUGGCAUGCCCAAUACUCUUGCCCAUCCUCGCUUGCUGCCCUAGGAUGUCCUCUGUUCUGAGUCAGCGGCCACGUUCAGUCACACAGCCCUGCUUGGCCAGCACUGCCUGCAGCCUCACUCAGAGGGGCCCUUUUUCUGUACUACUGUAGUCAGCUGGGAAUGGGGAAGGUGCAUCCCAACACAGCCUGUGGAUCCUGGGGCAUCUGGAAGGGCGCACACAUCAGCAGCCUCACCAGCUGUGAGCCUGCUAUCAGGCCUGCCCCUCCAAUAAAAGUGUGUAGAACUCCA